GCGACGGCCGCUGUGACGCUGCGGCGGCGGCGGGCGGGCGGCGGCGCGUGAGGCGCGCGAUCCCCGGUGUCUUGGGAGCAGUGCCCCGGCCCCCGCCGCUCCCGCCGCCGCCAUGUCGGGCCGGUCGGUCCGGGCGGAGACCCGCAGCCGGGCCAAGGACGACAUCAAGAAGGUGAUGGCGGCCAUCGAGAAAGUGCGGAAAUGACGGAAUCUCGCUCUGUCACCCAGGCUGGAGUGCAUUGGCGCAAUCUCGGCUCACUGCAACCUCUGCCUCUCAGGUUCAAGCAAUUCUCCUGCCUCAGCCUCCUGAGUAGCUGGGACUACAGGGAGAAGAAGUGGGUGACUGUGGGUGACACGUCCCUGAGGAUAUUUAAGUGGGUUCCUGUGACAGACAGCAAGGAGAAAGAAAAGUCAAAAUCGAACAGUUCAGCAGCCCGAGAACCUAAUGGCUUUCCUUCUGAUGCCUCAGCCAAUUCCUCUCUCCUUCUUGAAUUCCAGGACGAAAACAGCAACCAGAGUUCCGUGUCUGACGUCUAUCAGCUUAAGGUGGACAGCAGCACCAACUCAAGCCCCAGCCCCCAGCAGAGUGAGUCCCUGAGCCCAGCACACACCUCCGACUUCCGCACGGAUGACUCCCAGCCCCCAACGCUGGGCCAGGAGAUCCUGGAGGAGCCCUCCCUGCCCUCCUCGGAAGUUGCUGAUGAACCUCCUACCCUCACCAAGGAAGAACCAGUUCCACUAGAGACACAGGUCGUUGAGGAAGAGGAAGACUCAGGUGCCCCGCCCCUGAAGCGCUUCUGUGUGGACCAACCCACAGUGCCGCAGACGGCGUCAGAAAGCUAGCACCAUCCCGGCCCUCCGCCUCCUGGCCCUGCCUCUAUUUAUUGCAUUCUGGUUCUGGCCGCGCCGCGUUGCUGGGGUAAGGGCAAGCACUGGGGUCAAGAGCCUGCACACAUGAGCCUUCCGGGCUGGAAGGCUGGCGUAGGACUUGGGGCUGUAGCAUCAUCUUCCUGACCCUGGCACCUGUGUCUACUUGCUCCCGAGAAGAGGAGCGCUCAUGUCUUUUUUGCACCCCAAGUUGGCUGGAGCAUCGGCCACCCCAAGAUUCAUCUGUGACCUCCAGGCAGCAGUCUCUGCUCCAGAAUCUCUGGACGGAGCUGCUGGCAGCUUCUGCGAGAAGAGAGAGAUGUGGAAGGCACCUUCUAGAAGAGAGCGUGCCUCAGGUUACUUGAACUUGAACGGAGACUGUAGACUCCCGGACUUUCCCCUAGGACUGGGGGCCCUGUAGGCUGCUGUUGGAGGACUGGGUAGAGACAUUGGAGGGAAGGGAAGGGCUUUUCUCCACACAAGGGCAGAGAGUCCGUCUAGAUUUCUUGCUGUCCUGCCAGCUCUGCCCAUGCCUGAGGUGGUCCUACCUCUCACGGGCACCCUAGCUGCUGACAGCCCUUUGUGGCCGCCGUCCCCAUCCCCUGCCCUCAGCACACACAUCUGCACACACGCAGCUUUGUUCUCACCUCUACCUGUCAUUCCAGCAUCCCUGCCUCUUGUCACAAACUGCCCCAGCAAGAAUUUGAGGUUCUGACAACAGUACCCAUCCCCCACAGUACCCCUUCAGCUCAGUUUCUAGAAAGCUCCCUUUUCUUUGAAAUCUGCAUGUUGAAUUGAACUUUGUGAUUUUAUUUUUUGUUUCAAAAAAGUUUAAGAAAAUGGAAAUGGGCAACAGUGAGUGAAGACAUAUUUUAGCACUGAAUAGAAUAUUUUUAAAAUUAAACUAUUUGAAAUAUG